AAGCGGGGAGUCGAGGCGGCGAGCGCGCAGCUGGCCUAGUCUGCGGUCCCCAACUCCUGGAGUCCCCUGGGAGCUGCCGCUGCAGGCCCCCGAGCCGCUAGGCCCCGCCGCCAGGCCACCGCUGCUGCGGCAGCCAUGGCGGAAGUUCAUAGACGUCAGCAUGCUCGGGUUAAAGGAGAAGCCCCCGCGAAAUCCUCCACACUCCGAGAUGAGGAGGAGCUGGGGAUGGCGUCGGCCGAAACGCUGACCGUGUUUCUGAAGCUGCUGGCCGCCGGCUUUUACGGCGUGAGCUCCUUCCUGAUCGUGGUGGUGAAUAAGAGCGUGCUCACCAAUUACAGAUUUCCCUCCUCACUAUGUGUUGGACUUGGCCAGAUGGUGGCCACAGUGGCAGUUCUCUGGGUGGGAAAGGCGCUCAGAGUAGUCAAGUUUCCUGACCUUGACAGAAAUGUACCUCGAAAGACGUUUCCACUACCUCUACUAUAUUUUGGGAACCAAAUCACGGGACUGUUCAGCACAAAGAAACUGAACUUGCCAAUGUUUACAGUUCUGAGAAGGUUCUCCAUCCUGUUUACAAUGUUUGCUGAAGGAGUUUUACUCAAGAAGACUUUUUCUUGGGGUAUUAAAAUGACUGUAUUUGCAAUGAUUAUUGGAGCCUUUGUAGCUGCCAGCUCUGACUUGGCAUUUGAUCUGGAAGGAUAUGCUUUUAUUCUGAUAAACGAUGUCCUAACAGCAGCAAAUGGUGCAUACGUAAAACAAAAAUUAGAUUCAAAAGAGCUGGGAAAAUAUGGACUGCUCUAUUACAAUGCACUGUUCAUGAUUCUGCCCACCCUGGCCAUUGCGUAUUUCACAGGAGAUGCACAAAAGGCUGUGGAGUUUGAAGGCUGGGCUGACACCCUCUUUCUUCUGCAGUUCACCCUCUCCUGUGUGAUGGGGUUUAUCUUAAUGUACGCCACAGUACUCUGCACGCAGUAUAAUUCUGCUCUUACAACUACAAUAGUUGGCUGUAUUAAGAAUAUAUUAAUAACUUAUAUUGGAAUGGUCUUUGGUGGAGAUUAUAUUUUCACGUGGACAAACUUCAUUGGUUUAAAUAUCAGCUGUAUCUGCCACAGAGGUCUCUGUGAGUUAAGAGUUGGUAGUGCCACUUUGGGAGGCUGAGGCGGGCAGAUCACAAGGUCAAGAGAUCAAGACCACCCUGGCCAACAUGGUGAUACCCCGUCUCUACUAAAAAUACAAAAAUUAGCUGGAUGUGGUGGCAGGCACCUGUAGUCCCAGCUGCUCGGGAGGCUGAGGCAGGAGAAUCGCUUGAACCCAGGAGGCGGAGGUUGCAGUGAUCCGAGAUUGCGCCGCUGCACUCCAGCCUGGCAACAGAGUGAGACUCCGUCCCAACAAAAUAAAACAGUUGGUAGUGCUGUUGUUUGAAGAUUAGACAGAUGGAAAAUUGCUUGAAAAUUUUUUAAAAGGCAUAAACUUAGGCUUGCAUAAUGACUGUACCUUAUUUUCAAUAUGCAUGUUUUAACUUUUUAAAAGAAAAUCUUGUUGACCAGUACUAAUACCAGGAGUUCUACUUUUAAAAAAUGAAUAUUUAGGAUGAUCUAAUGUAUUAACACCAAUUUCAUAGUACUAGAAGGUAUCAACUUUAAUGUGAAUAUUUAUGGGGCCAAUAGAUUAGUUAAAGGGUCUCUGUUUGAAGUAGUAGAAGAUCCUGAUUUAGAAUCAUUUGGUAGUGUUGUAUAAAAAGUCAGAUAUAACCCCUCUCCCCUUCAAAUCUGGGCUUUUCCUCAUUUUCCCUUUCCCUUCCUUCUAGUUUUCCCCUUCCCCAAAGCUGCUAGAGAGCAAAUUAUAGUUCCUUUCCAAAGCGUUUACUCAUCACUGCGUAACACAUAGUAUGCUCGUUGAUGAAUAUUCAGUUCUCUUCAGGUGGUUCAUGAAUUGCCCUUUCCGAAAAUCUAUAUUUGAUAAUGAUCGAGUCAGUAAUAAAGAUGAAAUUAAAUAUAUUUUAUUGUUGCCUCAAGUUACAACCAUGUGGCAAUAGUGUGCCCCCUCUUUCAUAAUGUUACAUUCCUUGCUCUAUGGUCUGAAUGUUUGUGUUCCCCCAGUUUGUUGAACUCUCAACUCCCAAAGUCAUGGUAUUAGGAGGUAGGGCUUUGGGAGGUGAUUAGGUCAUGGAAUUGGCAUCCUCAUGAAUGAGAUUAGUGCCCUUAUGUAAGAGAUCCCAGAGCAUGAUGAGAAGAUACUGUCUGUGAACCAGAGAGCCCUCUCUAGACAUUGAACCUGCCUUGAUCUUAGACUCCCCAGCCUCUAGGACUGUGAGAAAUAAAUUUCUGUUGUUUAUAAGCCACCAUUUAUGGUAUUUUGUUAUAGCAACCCAAAUGGAGUAAGACGUUUAUAAUUAUAGUACCUUACCUUUUGUCAGCAGUACAUCUCCCCUCUGGUUCUGAGUGUCAGGGCUGACAGGGAAGGUAGGGGAGAAGAGAAUGAAGAGAAGAUUAUCCGUGUAAUCUCAUUUAAUCCUCAGACAAGCUUAGAUAGAUAACAUUAUUCUUAUUUGAUGAAUACAGAAAUGGAUUAAUUAAUUUGCCCAGGGUCACAUAGCUAGUGUAGAUUGAACAUCUGUGAUCCAAAAUGCUCCAAAAUCUGGAAUUUUUGAAUGAUAACAGGAUGAUCAAAGGAAAUGUUCUUUGGAACAUUUCAGAUUUGAGAUUUGGAUGCUUGACUGGUGAGUAUAAUGCAGAUAUUCCAAAAUUUGAAAUUGGAAACCCUUCUGGUCCCAAGCAUUUUAGAUAAGAGAUACUCAACCUAGAGUACAUUCAGGAUUUGAACCAAGACCUAACCGUAGAGUCAGUGUUUUUUCCAAUACACUGACUAUGCUGGGAAUAUAGGGUCUGGAAUUAUCAUUAGGGCUAAGCCUGGAAUAAAUUACAGGACAUUCUUUGUCUUCUUCUAUCCUGUGCUUCCCCAGUAUUCCUAUCCAGUUUAAAUAGGAUUAAUGUGAACAUCAAAGAUCAUCUUAACAGGAAAAAUAAGAAAGCAUUUUUAUUUUUUAGGCUGUUGUGGGAAGGCGAAGCUAGAGGAAGGUAGGAUGAAAGAAAGGAGAGGUAGCCCUUCUACUUUGUUUUGGGGUGGGUUUGGAGGCAAAGGGAAAUUGACUGUCAUGUGGGUGGACGUACAUGUGAACCUUAAAGAACUUUUAGCUUCAGUCAAAAAAGACUUCAGUAAGCCAUCUUCUUGGGUCCAGGCCAGCUACCAGGGAAGUAGUCUACUUGAGGGACUAGAAAAACCAGAAAAGUUUCUAGGAGAGUCAUAUCAAAUUCCAGAAAAAAUUAAAUGGGAAAAAGCUGCUGGAUGAAGGAAAAGAUGAAGCUCUAUGAACAUUGGCAUAAGAAUUGGGUUCAUGCUAGGCGCGGUGGCUCACACCUGUAAUCCUAGCUCUUAGGGAGGUAGAGGCGGGAGGAUAGCUUGAGCCCAGGAGUUCACGACCUGCCUGGGCAAUAUAGCGAGACCCCAUUUUCCACAGAAAGGGGGGGAAAGACAAUAAAAAGUGUAAGAAUUGGGUUCAUGAGGCCCCCUUUCCUCAAGUGGGGUGAUAGGGGAUACUCAGUUCAGCAGUUACUUAUUGUGUUGCUAAAAAGUGUCAGGCCAAUUGCAAGAGACUCUGUACAGCUAAAAGAAUUAAGGCCGUGGGAAAUUAACAAGAUGAUAAGGACAGAGUGAGGAUGGAUAACUAGUAUUCAGUGGCACAAGGGUCAUAAGGGAGGCAGCAGUUGGAGUGGAGAAAGACUGACCUAGGUUGUAUUCUGGCCCAUCAGUAGGAUGCUUUGUGACCCUGAGCAAUUUAUCUUAUGACUCUGGGACUUUCCUCAUCUAUAAAAUGGACACCUUGGAGGGAUAUUGUACCUUGCAGGAAUAUUGCAAAAACAGGAAAUGUAUGUAAAAUGCUUGACAAGUAGACUUUAAUAAUUUGAUUGCUCUUAAGUGCCGUGAGGUGCAGAUGAGGAAAAGGAAGAAUCUGGUUGGGAAGGUUAAAUUGGAAAAGGCUUUAUUUUGGGUUGAUUGGAGUCUCAGAGAAUGGCUAGUAUUAUGCGAGCGUGUGCAGUAAAGAACAAGCGCCAGUGCCUGAUCCUGCUUUCUUCCUAGUGGGAACAAGAGCUAGGCGUCUCUCACCCUUCUGCAGCUGGUCUGGGGCUGAUGUCAGAGCCCAGAGAACAGAACUAAUUUCAAAUAAGCAGCAAGUUCAUGAGUCAAGUGGUUAGGCAGAAGAUGAGGGCCAAAACCAGGGCAGAAGAAUUGGCGCCCAGGUCAGGCAUCCAGCUGGCUGGAAUCCAAGGGAGUCCUGGGUGGCAGUCUCAGUGGAAGAGCCAGGGAGGACAGGGCAGGAGUGGUCGGAUCUGUGAGCUCCUCCAGACUACUUUCCACUUAGUGAAUCGGGUAGGAGGCUGCGUAUCCUAGGUGAGUUUGAGGUCCCCACAGAGAAUGGACCAAGUAAUCAUUGUCACCAAAGAGGGAUCCUUCCUGGUGGUAGGUGCGAUGGAUAAGUGAGGGGUACCAGCAACCACCUGUCAUAGGCUGACGGCCCAGAUGAUAAGUUCCCCACUGUGAACUUGCUUUUAGUCAGAGAAAAAUCAGCUCUGUGAAUCUCCUAGGGUCUGCAUAUUUAACUAAUUUGGGAUGUUUCCUAUUAAUGCCUAUUUUUCGAAAUGCAAAAAAAUACAAGUAAAAAUUUACCUGUAAUGUCAGCAUCCAGCUGUAACCACUGUUAAUAUUCUUGGUGUGUUCCUUACAGACUUUUGUCUAUUCCAGUGCAUAUUGAUAUACAUACUCAUGUUCAUUUAAAUAAAAUGGGAUUAGACAAUGCUUGAUGUUUUAUGAUAUAUUUUCUCAUAAAAAUUUAAGCUGUCUUACAAAAUUUAAUGUGUCAAUGCCUGUUUAUAUUUUAUACCAUUUUAAUGGAUGCAUAGUACUUCAUUGUAUGAAUUUCCCCACUGUGAAACUUUACUCUUCAUCUAAUUUUUUGGUGUAAGUUUUUUUACUGAGUAGAGUGUUUACACUAAAACCCUCCCUUCCUCCAUCUCUGAUAGUGGCUUUCUGUUUUGCAGCAUUGCUGGGAGCCUGGUAUAUUCCUAUAUCACUUUCACUGAAGAGCAGCUGAGCAAACAGUCAGAGGCUAAUAACAAGCUGGACAUUAAGGGGAAAGGAGCAGUGUGACCAGAGGAUUGCUUCAUCUGAUACGUAGGCCUAAGUUUUUAAUCAACUCAGAACACUGGCAGUUCCUACAGAGACACUGAGGUGUCUUGAUUAUGGAGGAAAUAACCAUUCCUUUGCACUUGUACAAUCUGAGGAUUGAUUGCUGCCUUUUAAAAUUUUAUGAAGAGAGAAACUUAUAAUUGACUCUAUUUUAAAUAUGUUGUUUGAAUUAAUUUAUAUCAGACUGGAAAAGGUACUGGGCUUUUUAAUUUAUUUUUCUUAUAUGCCGACAGUGAAACAUCAGUGUUUUGAAAGUAUUUUAUUUCAUAAUUUGAUAUCCAGGUGUCCCUGAGAGCUGCAUAUGUAAUGUUUGCCAACUGGAGCUUCAUCAUUCAAAUUGUUGCUGCAUCUGGAGGCAGUUUAGCCUUUCCUCUGCUGGAAAUGCAGACGAAUAUGUGAAAUUUCUCUUCUUUGAAUCUUAUUUCUUAUGAUUGCAUUGUCUUCAUCAUAUCAUCAUUCCAUUUGCCAAGGAAAACAACUUUGGCACUAUAAAAAUAUGUGGGGCUUUGAAGUGUAUUGCUAUCUAUGUUGGCUUCCCUGACUUUCAUAGGAUGAGCAGAGUGCAUUCCUUGAAAACAUGUUCUUUUUUUGUUGUGUAGAAUGGGGAUAAUGAAGGGGGUGAGAAAGUAGGCCUUUUACUAAUUUUUCAUCUAUUUGACUUAUUGAUUCAACUAAAAUGUUUUAAGUAUAUGUGCCAGGCAUUGUGCUAAAUGCUGGGGAUACAGAGAUGUUUGCAGAGGUAGUUGAAACAUCUCACUCCUGCCAUAGUGACUCAGGUAAGGUUGAGAAUUUAGCUCUGUUAAUCUAUUCAGAAGAUGUCACUAAGAGUAAGUUGUUUCAGCACUCAAAAGCCGCAAAUCUGUAAAUUGGAUUAAGAACACCUGCCCUACCUACCCGGCAAUAGUGUGAAUCCAAAUGCUGCAAUGUGAGAUGAGGUACAAGUAAAGAGCUGUGUUUUGUAAACCAGUGCAGCUCAGCAUUGACUCCCUCUCUAAGUGAAAAUUGCAGACAGGCAAGUCUGUUUUCCCUUGCCACCUUCCUUUGGGUUUGGUUGCUCUUUGGAUGAAUAUGAUGAGGUCCCACAUUUCUGAAUUUAUUGGUUUGAGGGGAAAGGCUGGUUAGACGUCUUUGUAUUGUCAAUGGUUGGUUUUUCUCUGGCAGUGUCAGUGUUAGAGCUAUCAUCUUCCUUCUUAAAUGGCAUGAGCAAUGAGCAAACUUCCCUCCUUUCAACAUUCUCACCUACAUCAUGUGCCCCUUGGCUCACCUACUGAGCUUGCCAACUUCUCUCAAAACCAAUGCUGCAUUUUGGGAGAGCAGCUGUGAAUGGGCACUGCCUAAAUUGCCUCUUGGGGUAAUCUGGAGGGUGGAGGUGUUAACUCAAACAUAACCCUAUGACUUGACUCAGAGAUAUCCAUUGACUUUGAGGAUUAGUGUGUUUGCUCAGGCCAGUUGUACAGCCAGUGUGCAAGAGAUUUGGUACCUUUGCACUAAUGCACACACCAGUGUCUAUUUCAUUGGGUUUGGAAUCCACUGGACUCUGUUGACCUAAACAGUUAGGGUUUUGAUUUUUUUUGAUAUGCAAAUUUAUAUUGAGAUCAUUUUCAUAUUCCUGUCUUUUGGUUUGUCUUUACUAAAGCUUGGCUGGUGGUGCUGUGUCCCUAGAAUUAUCCCUGCAACCAACUCCCAAGUUACAAGCUUCAUUAAGAGCCUUAGACUCACUUUUUUCUAGCAUCUUCUGACCUGAGAAAAUUCCACUGGGAGUAAAGGAUAGUAUCUUGUGUCAUAUGGGUCUUACUCUCCCUAUUUUACCAAUGAGAAAACAAAACUCAGAGAAAGAUGACUUGCUAAUACAUCAAACCCAUGUCCUUUUUAUUGAACUAUGCUGCCAUUUAAUUAACCGCCCUUCCCCUCUGAGGGAGUAAGGAAACAGAUCCUGAGUUCACUUGAGCACUUUCAAAAAAGCAAGCAGUUGAUUGAAUUUGGUGUCAGAGAGGAGCAUACUUUGCAAAUCAGGAAGAGUGACAGCUUACCCUGUCCUGGAACCCUUAUCCCACUUCCAGGCUGACUUUAGUUGAUAAUGCACUUCUGGCUGUAAAUGUUGCCAACACUUCCUGGUUUUGCUUAGGUACAGUGAAAGGGCAUAGUGAGAGCUAUUUUUAGUGAUUCUGUUCUUUCUGUCAGCAACAUGAAGGAGGGACGUUUGAAUAAUUUUUGUUGUAGAAUAUUUCUUCAUGAAAGGCUUUUGGGUGUCUUUAACAGGUGUUGGGCUAGAGCCCCACCAGGAGUUGAACUGCCUCUUGGGGGUCAGGUUCCCUAGGAGAUCUGUCACCUCUUCAGGAGUAUUUGAGAACAUUGUGUAGUUACAGCUUCACUAAAUGCACGUGACAGGCUUCUGUGCCUUGGGAGCCCUGGCUUAUGCUGAAACUUCUGGCUGACCAGAGCAGUACAGCAACUUUGCCCUGUCUGUGUUCUGCUUCCUGGAUGCAUCCUUCAGCCACUAACCAGCAUUGCAAGAUGGAGCAGGGUGAACAAGCUGGAGACUGAAUAGUCUUUUGGAGUUUGCGUUUUGAUUAUUGCAGGCGUGUUACAAUAUACUGGUGAUUUACCUGGUACUGUGGCACCUCCCAGAAAGUCUGGUUUUUGCCCCAUGUUUGAUAUUUACUAGGCAGAAAUUCUUUGUCCUGUUAACUGCCUCCUGGGAGAAAAAGAGGCAAUACAGAGUUAAAUCCUUAAUUUGCCCACUGAGACAGAUGAGCUGUGGUAUUCCAAAAGACAAAUUCUAUGACUAGUGUCUCCUGUUCAAUGUAAGUGAGACCCUCUUUGGCCAAUCUGCUUCUAGUCAAGGCUAAAUGGAUUGGAAUAACCCUAGUUGGCCAGGCUACACAUUGCCAGCAUGUCCCGUUGAGUUUUAAUUGCCUCAUGUGGCUGUGGACUUUAUGAGUCAAUCAUUUGUAGGCUCCAGUUUGCACCUAGUUUUUUUUUUUAAAAAGUGCAUUUACACGCUUUUGGUAGUCCUGUUUUAUCAAGAAUCCAUGGAGGGUUUUGGUCAGUACAGCUGGUGCAGGAUCCUCACGGAGAAACAGUGGAGUUUCACAUUGAGUUGGUUUGAAAUGGCACCCCAGGACUUUGGGCCUGCCUUACUUGAUAGCCUCGUUCAGUGAGCAAAGACUUAGUGAGCAGCUCUUGUAUGCCAAGUAUUUUGCUAAGCUCUGGAAAAAAGAUAAACAAGACAUGGUUCUUGCUUUCAAGGAGUGUGUAAUUCUUUAGCCAGAUAUGGAAACCUGGACCCUGAGUGGGAGAAAGGAGACAGAUGAAAGGAGUCCGUGAUUUUGUAACCAAGAGCUGCCUGCAUGGUUAUGAGUAUCACUGAUUUUAGGGACGCCCCACAGAGCUAAAGCAUUUUUUUAAUCCGAGAGGACUUUUGUAACUCAUAUUAGUUAAUCUUCUAGCUCUGAGAUAGCAACACAGCUCUUAGAAUUCUGUAAGUAGCUUGAGGCCUCCUCCUCUACUGUACAUGUUCUUGCUUUCCCAAAAUUGUAAGUUUGGUUUUUCCUAUGAACAAGACUGUAAUUGAUUUUUCUCUCCCUGAGGAAAAAAGUUCGGAAUAAAUGAGACAUGGAUAUGAAACUACUUAGCACAAUGCCUGGUACAUAUUAGGCCCUCAGCAAAUGUGGCUACCGUGUCAUUAUUUCAUGGUGAGACUCAAGGCAAAACAAGAUUCUUAAUUUAUGCUCCGUAAAUGCUAGAGGCUUGGGCAAUACGGUCUGUCCUGAAAAACAGGACUCUGUGUCUCAUUGCCUCUAGAAUCCUUAGGUAGCAGUUUCUGUUCACUGUCUUUUCUUUUUUAAAAAUAUCUGCUGGACACAAUUACGGCCAUUACAUGAUGCAGGUGAUUCUACCUAUUUUUUAAAAAGAACAAAAUUUCUUUUAUAUUGUGACAGUACAUUUUAAUAAAGGAAAAUUAUUUUCUUCCCCCUACUCCCCCUCCUUUUUUUUAAAAAAAAAAAAAAAAAAGAAAGAAGGUCUUGCUCUGUCGCCAGCCAGGCUGGAGUGUAAUGGCGUAAUCAUAGCAGCUCACCACAGUCUCAAACUCCUAGGCUCAAGUGAUCCUCCUGCCUUAGCCUGCUAAGUAGCUACGACUAUAGGCAUGUGCCAUUACGCCUGGCUCGUUUCUUCCUUUUUUUUUUUUUUUCUGGUAAAGACAGGGUCUCACUCUGUUGCCAGACUGGUCUCAAACUCCUGGCCUCAAGUAACCCUUCUGUCUCAGCCUCCCAAAGUGCUGGGAUUACAGGUGUGUGCCACAUGUCCGGCCAGGAAAAUUAUUUUCUAUCUUAAAGAAACAUAGUUACAUUUUAGAAUGUCAAUUCAGUUAAAUCUUUCUCAGUUUUUACCUUUAGAUGGCUCCUGGAAAGGCCAGCGUUCCUUUUCCCCUCUCUGAAUUGAAAGCACUUGACCCCAUGCUGCCCCUGCUUCCAGGCCUGUCUCAGUUGUCAUAUAUUGUGAGUCCCUGGCACCAUUACUGUUUUCUAAGCCAGUCUUCUAGGUCUUACUUUCAGGAUGCUGCUUCAUGGCAUGAGGAUAUAGUUUACAGUGUUGUAGUUUUUUUUUUUUUAAAGCUUUGUUCUUUAAAAAUACUUUUUAAAAAGAAAUCUACUGGUUAGAUUUAUUGUCUCACAAAAAUGUUUUUAGAGAUUAUUUUUUUCACAAAUGUUUUCUUUCUCAUGCUGAUGAUCAACUGAUUUUUGUCUACAGGUGUUAGCUUCUCACAGUAUUUUUUCAUUUUAGAGUCUAUUUACCAAAUGACCAUUUUUAGUGUUAAAAGGUACUGAGGAAUUGAGGUAUGUAAAUCAGGUGACAUAAACAUGAAAAUUAUGUGCCUAAAUAUUUUUGUAAUGGUGUAAAAUAAAUACUUUUUCCUGAAAA